UGUGUUCUGAUUUAAUUUCAGCAAAUGGUAAUAAGACGAAUGAGAAAGCAAGAGAAAAAGGAAGAGGUGCAGAGUCACCAUAGUUGGAAUCCUGUAAUCACAGAGGCUGGGCUUCCUGGUAAUACAAGUGGUGACUCCAGCCAUAAUACUCUGAGACCAUCUCAUUGCACACUGGCCAUGCACGGGGCACAGCUCUAAGCACUUCAUCUCUACUGUCUCAUUUAAAGCCCACAGACCUCCCAGAGACAGAGACCAACUGUGAUCCCUACCGUGUGGAUGGUGACACGGAGCACAGAUCGUUUCAAUCAUUCACCCAAAGUCACACAGAUUAUAUGGUUAAGCUGGGAUUUGAUCCCAGGACUCUCUGACUCUACAGCCUGAGUUGUCAAUCUUCCUUUCUUACCUUGAGAUAAGGAAGUAUGGAGGAAAGAGUGAAAGGACCAGGUCACUGCCCAAGCGCCGCACUGCACAGUGACCUCAGACCCAUGUGGCAUCCACAGGUGUUGCCAAUCCUGGGGUCCCAUUCCCGGAGCUGGGGUGGGGAGGACCCUACCUGGCCCAUGGACUAGCGGCUCUGGCUGGUGGCACGUGUCAUGUGCUAUCUCUGCAUGGCAGCAGCCGGUUUUAAGACAUGUUCUGACAAAUCAUCUCUCCCAGGUGAGAACAGCAGCUCACCCUCAGCCUGGUAUUAGCAAAUGGAUUUUUUUGUCCGAGAUGGAGUUUCACUCUUGUUGCCGAGGCUGGAGUGCAAUGGCAUGAUCCCAGCUCACUGCAAUAUCCACCUCCCGGGUUCAAGUGAUUCUCCUGCCUCAGCCUCCCGAGUAGCCAGGAUUACAGGCACCUGAUACCACGCCCGGCUAAUUUUUUGUAUUUUUAGUAGAGAUGGGGUUUCGCCAUGUUGGCCAGGCUGGUCUCGAACUCCUGACCUCAGGUGAUCCACCUGCCUCGAGGCCUCCCACAGUGCUGGAUUACAGGCGUGAACCACUGUGCUCGGCCAGCAAAUGGAUUUUGAACCUGUUCUGUGAAGUCUUACAGAAAAGGAGAGCUGGGAAGGAGAUGGAUGUGAGGCCCCUGGAGAAAGACAGACCUGGGCCCAAGCCUGGGACCUGCAGGUUCCGUCAUCGCUGCGAGACUCGGUCAUUCAUCAGCAGGAUGGGGCUCCCCAGAGUAGCUCCCUGGCAGGAUUGGUGAGGAUGAAAAUAGAGAUGCCUGUCCCAGCCAGCACUCCAGAGGCGUUGGCAAUCACUGCUAAAGGUGACACACUAUUUUUGGUUUUUAGGGGUAAAGCAAGACCUUAGCAAGGUCCCAGGCUGCAGGGCUGAAUGCUGUGGUGGCUACAGGGGUGAGCGAGAUGCCUGGCUCCGGGAUCCUAAAACCAGACAGUGUCUGUAGAGGGAAAACAUCCUCCAUGUCACUGGAAGGGCCACCAUCCAGGGUGCACGUCACCAGGGCUACAGGGAAGGGACAUGGUGCUCUAGGCUCAGAGAAGGGAGGGAUCUCCCUGGCUCGGGCGGGGUAGGAAGAUCCUUAUGAAGAAAUGACAUUUGCAGAAGGCCUCUAAGAAAGUGGAGGGUUUUCACAAACCAAAAGCAAGCAGAAAGCACGGCUGGAGUGAACCUUGCUAUGGGGGCUCACAGGGUUGCACCUUCUCACCAGAGCAUAGGGCAGGGGUGGGGAAGGAAUGAGAGCCACAGACGGGAAUGAAGUGGAAGGUAAGGUCUCAAAGGCAAGGCUGAGGGACCUGCCCUUCACUCCAACUUGCCCCAGGCCUAGCAAGGUGAGCAGGGAUGGUUUCCUGGAGGGAAACAUCAGCUCCGAUCAGAGAGGAAAUCCCAGGCCACCCCCUGCCUUUGUGGCAGGAAGCACUCAAGGCCUCUGGCUAGGAUCUGGAGCCCCUGAGGCUGAGGUCAGGUGGCAGGGCCAGUGUCACCCUCCUCUGCCCCAGGGUGAGUGUGGCACUGAACCCCAGCACCAUUUGUGCUUUCUGUCCCCCUGGAUCUUGGGCCCGGCUGCCCCCCAAUGCAGGGAUGCCCACCACGGCCGUCCUCCUGGAUGCAAUCCUUCCCAGCCCUCAGGCAUCUGCCAGCCUCCUCCUUCUCUGGCCUUCCCACAUCUCAGCCUGGUUCCUGGACACAGAUGCCGUGGUGUGCUGGAGCCGGCUCCUACUAGCUGGCAGGAGUCAAUCUGCACAUCUCUCCCCAAAACCAUGAUCAGCGAAAUCCUCUUAGUAAGCUUGAAGUUGGCCAUGCUGGGAGUAUUUACACCAUGGGAAGUGGCAAAUGCUACCAGUUAGGUAGGGCUACUCUCUCUCAGAGAGCCAGUUGUUAGACUUACUAGCACACCUCUACACAGACAAUGCUAGCCAAGCUGGUCUGGAUUAGAACUCAUUUAAAAGCUGCUCUCUCUGCAUGCUCAGGGUGAGCAGAGCUGCUGAAAUGGCAGAGUGAGGGACAGCUGAUGAGUAGGAGAGACCCUCCAGCUGGGUCACUGAGGGUCUUCCAGGAGAAAUGACACUUUCUAUUCAGCAUACUUGUCAGUGGUUUCAGUGAGGAUGCCACUCGCCUGGAGGUCUCUGUAUUGACUUCACAGGUUCUAAUACCUCUCUCUUCAAUAAUAUUCUAAAUUCCUAGAAAGCAGGGGGCGCCAGCUGUGCCACUAACCUUGCUGCUUUAUUUCUCUGGACCUGAACUCCCUCAUGCGCAAAAAGGAAGAUGGUGCUAGAAAGGAGCUUCUCAAGCCCUAAUGCAUCUACGAAACACCUGGGAGCUCGUUACACAUGCAGAUGCUGGACCUAACCUCACACUCGCAAAAUCCAGCUCUCCAGGCGUGAGGCUGGGAACCCAUAUCGGUUCCAACUCAGGUGGUCUCAAAACCACAUGGAGAAACACUGAGCCAGGCCAAUGUGUUCCAACCCUCAGAUUUCAGAAGGAGACAAUGUCACCAGCAGCUGAUUGGGCGUCUAUGUGAGUGUCUGUCCUCAGAUCUCAGAAGGAGAUGAUGUCACCAGCAGCUGGUUGGGUGUCCAUGUCCUCAGAUUUCAGAAGGAGACAAUAUCAUCGGCAGGUGUUUAGGUGUCCAUGUGAGUGUCUGUCCUCAGACCUCAGAAGGAGACGAUGUCACCGGCAGGUGGUUGGGUGUCCAUGUCCUCAGAUCUCAGAAGGGGACGAUGUCACCGGCAGCAGGUUUGGUGUCCAUGUCCUCAGAUCUCAGAAGGAGACGAUGUCACUGGCAGGUGGUUUGGUGUCCAUGUCCUCAGAUCUCAGAAGGGAACGAUGUCACCAGCAGCAGGUUGGGUGUCCAUGUCCUCAGAUCUCAGAAGGAGACGAUGUCACCGGCAGGUGGUUGGGUAUCCAUGUCCUCAGAUCUCAGAAGGGGACGAUGUCACCGGCAGGUGGUUGGGUGUUCAUGUCCUCAGAUCUCAGAAGGAGACGAUGUCACCGGCAGGUGGUUUGGUGUCCAUAUCCUCAGAUCUCAGAAGGAGACGAUGUCACCGGCAGGUGGCUGGGUAUCAAUGUCCUCAGAUCUCAGAAGGGGACGAUGUCACCGGCAGGUGGUUGGGUGUUCAUGUCCUCAGAUCUCAGAAGGAGACGAUGUCACCGGCAGGUGGUUUGGUGUCCAUGUCCUCAGAUCUCAGAAGGAGACGAUGUCACCGGCAGGUGGUUGGGUGUCCAUGUCCUCAGAUCUCAGAAGAAGAUGAUGUCACCGGCAGGUGGUUGGGUAUCCAUGUCCUCAGAUCUCAGAAGGGGACGAUGUCACUGGCAGGUGGUUUGGUGUUCAUGUCCUCAGAUCUCAGAAGGAGACAAUGUCACCAGCAGGUGGUUUGGUGUCCAUGUCCUCAGAUCUCAGAAGGAGACAAUGUCACCGGCAGGUGGUUGGAUAUCCACGUCCUCAGAUCUCAGAAGGGGACGAUAUCACCGGCAGGUGGUUGGGUGUUCAUGUCCUCAGAUCUCAGAAGGAGACGAUGUCACCGGCAGGUGGUUUGGUGUCCAUGUCCUCAGAUCUCAGAAGGAGACGAUGUCACCGGCAGGUGGUUGGGUAUCCAUGUCCUCAGAUCUCAGAAGGGGACGAUGUCACUGGCAGGUGGUUUGGUGUUCAUGUCCUCAGAUCUCAGAAGGAGACAAUGUCACCGGCAGAUCUCAGAAGGAGACAAUGUCACCGGCAGGUGGUUGGAUAUCCACGUCCUCAGAUCUCAGAAGGGGACGAUAUCACCGGCAGGUGGUUGGGUGUUCAUGUCCUCAGAUCUCAGAAGGAGACGAUGUCACCGGCAGGUGGUUGGGUAUCCAUGUCCUCAGAUCUCAGAAGGGGACGAUGUCACCGGCAGCUGGUUGGGUGUUCAUAUGGGCUGGUUCACGCGGUUGGGCAAUGAUUAUUGUGAGGUCUUCAGCUCCUCCUUCUCCUACUAUUACUGCUACUACUACUGCUGCUGCUGCUACUUUUAG